AUAACACACCUGGUGCCUCCCUUCCUUUUCUUUUCCCACUGAGCCUUUGACAUUUAGUUUCACUGCGGUCAGGUAUGAGCAAGUACAUGAUUUUCCUGUACCACCCAAUUCACAUCAUGCAAAAGUCUCACAGAGAGGGACAUGAAGAUCUGCAAGAACAAAUGUUAAAACAGACAGAUGUGCAUUUUACAAGGAUGUUGUUUAUCUUGAAAUUCUCAUCACUGCAUCAUUGCUACUGCCCAAGGGUUGAAUUAAGGGCAAAACAUUUCAGAGACAGAUUUGAAAUUACCUAAUUAUCCUAGACAUGUUGUAAUGUUCCCUUUUAUAAUGCCUGGCUCAAAAAGCUUGAUGUCAGGUUACAGAACUGUAUGCAUUCUUUGAUUGUAAUUGUGUUAACAAUAGUAAAAAAUCUUGCAUACAAUCAAGACCAGAAAGAAAUCCAGAUGCUAAUUGUUGUUUUGUUAAGUAAUAAAAUGGUGGUAAGCAAUGCUUUUUCUCUUUUUGCUUUUUUUUCUUUUUCUUAUCUGUAAUGUGACAAUUCUUUAUUACUUGGAAAGUACAUUUUAUGAGAACUGUGAAAACUCGGAAAGUAGAAGUUCAAAGUAUUUUACAUUUAAUAACAUCUAGCUAAUCCUUAUGAUAUCUAGAUAAGGUGCUACUUUACAUCUUAUGAAAUAGCACAAGCCUUAGGCAAACUUCUGUAGUAGAAGAAAUGUGUUCUGAGACUUCUGAGACUUCUAUCUUGCUAGUUUUUAAGAUAUCUUUUCUCCCAGAAACCUGGUGUCCAGUGUCCCUCUCAAAUCUGCCAAAGGACAGUAGCUUAAAGAUUUACUUAUCUCAGGGGAGUUGCAUUUUUAUAGCCAUCAAUGGCAUAUAAUUUGGAAUUAGAGGCACAGGCAAGCAGGCCUUCCGAAUCUCUGUGAGCCACAAGACCCGAUGGCACCCUGAAAUCAAACUUCUGUAGACUGGGAGCCUUGUUGACCGCUGUUCCCCAAUUCUGACAGAUCAAAGCUGUUGCUAAUUUGUUAACCAGAGGCAGUGAUACAAAUGGAAGAUGCAACUAUUCAUUCUGAGGGACGCAUAAAAGUCUGAUUAAUCUAAGGAGCAGUCAUUGCCCAAGCAGUUAAGGAGAAUAUUUUUGGAAAGGCAGACAUCAGAAGCUAAGCAGAGUACAAAUUUCCACCCUCUACUUACUGUAUUAAUCAUAUCAGCUCUCACUCUUCGUAGAUGCUGCCCUGCUCGAAAGCACUGGUUAUUUAGCUGGGAGUCAGGAGAACCCAAACCCUCCCUGGGCAUAGACAAAUUGUAAUUUUAUAGCAGACAGCCUCUAAAAUGUUUCUACAUCCACAACAGUUGACACUGCCAGGCGCAGUGGCUCAUGCCUCUAAUCCCAGCACUAUGGGAGGCUGAGGUGGGAGGAUUGUUUGAGCUUAGGAGUUCGAGACCAGGCUGGGCAACAUAUUAUUUAAAGAGACUAGGUCUCUUUAGUAAUAACAAGGCCAGGUGCGGUGGCUCACGUCUAUAACCUCAGGGGGCAUCACCUGAGGUCGGGAGUUCAAGACCAGCCUGACCAACGUAGAGAAACCCUGUCUCUACUAAAAACACAAAAUUAGCCAGGCGUGGUGGUGCGUGCCUGUAAUCCCAGCUACUCGGGAGGCUGAGGCAGGAGAAUCACUUGAACCCGGGAGGCGGAGGUUGCGCUGGGCCGAGAUCGUGCCAUUGCACUCCAGCCCAGGCAACAAGAGCGAAACUCCGUCCCCCCCAAAAUAAUAAAAACUAAUUAGCCAGGCGUGGUGGCGUGCCUGUAGUCCCAGCUACUUGGGAAGCUGAAGUGGGAGGACCACCUGAGCCCGGGAAGUGGAGGCUUCAGUGAGCCAUGAUUGCACCACUGCACUCCAUCCUGAAGCCUAUCUUAAAAAAAAAAGAAGAAAAAGUGACACCUAUAAAAAAACUCACAUACUUAUAGUCCAGAAAUGUGCUGUCCAGUAAGGUAGCCACUAGCCACAUGUGGCUAUCUAAAUUUACUAAAAUAAAAUUUUAAAUUCACUUCCUUAGUUACACUAGCCAUAUUUCGUGUUCAGUAGCAACAUGAGGCUAGUGGCUACUGUACUGGAGAGUGGAGAUACAGAACAUGUCCAUCAUCACACAAAGUUCUACUGGACAGUGCUGGUCCAGAAGAGAAUAACUUCAAAUUGCAUUUUUGGUACAGGCAUGUAUAAGCCCGCACUUCCACAUUCUGUAAAGGCAUAAAGCGCCUCCCUACCCCAGGGCAUGUCUGUACAGUCAUUAAAUGGUCUGACUCCAGCACUUCUUUCUACUUAAUCUCUAAAUCUCUAAAUCUUGACACGCACAUCGCACACAACACAAACUCUAUUUUAGCCCACCUCCCUCUUCACUGACUCUUCAUGGUAGGUUUAGUUCCCAUAAUCCAUGAAAAUGCCUAGCUCCUUGUCACUAGAGCUUGUUUUGGAAACCUGCCUACAGUGUAACAAGCUGGAAUGUGAAGAGGGAUGCAUCUAUUUGUGUUGCUGAGUCAUUGAAUUGACUGAAGCUUCAAGGACUAGGGGGUGCUGAGCAGAAAUGAAAACACACAAUCCUUUCUGUUAGAGAUUUGCUCUUUUCGUAUUGGCAUGUAAACAAGUAAGUCACUAAGUGAACUGACGUCACAAUUUAGUUUUAGGAAGAUGCUUUUCCCAGGCACGAUUUGAACUCAGUGGUUUCCUGAAUCUAGCAAAGUAUGCUGCUUUGUUUUCUCUUAGAUUAAUUUUGCCUAAUUUUAAAGCUUUGAUUCUCUUUUUACGAAGACGAAAAUAAAUCUCUCUAGUCUGGGCCUUUUUCGUUUCCCAGGAUUAUGAUUAAAAUUAUCACUAACUUUUAGAUAGUCCAGCACGCACCGGAUGACUCUGAAGCCGGUUGGGCAGUGGAGAUCGGGAAGAACAUGAAAAAGCUUCAAAGCUUUUGGUUGAGGACAUCGGGAGAUGUAAACCCCAAACGCGGGUUUUACUUCUCCCCUCCACCCCUCCCCGCAAACCCAUGCCUACUCGUUUUGACUGCUCAGCAAUUCUGAGGCCAACCAUUUGCAACGGCGAGGAGCAGGGGCUGAUUUGAUUUGUAUCCACUGUCACCAGCACUGCUCACUUAGGACUUUCUGGAUCCGGACCCAGGCAGCGCACACUGGACUCUUGAGGAAGAAGGAGACUCUAAUUUUGGAUUCCUUGGUGGAGGAAAAUAAAACACUCUGGUCUUGCCGCCAACGAUGCAAGUGUGACUGCUGGCGUCUUCAUGAGCUCCAGAGGUCACAGCACGCUACCAAGGACUCUCAUGGCCCCUCGGAUGAUUUCCGAGGGAGACAUAGGAGGCAUUGCUCAAAUCACCUCCUCUCUAUUCCUGGGCAGAGGCAGUGUGGCCUCCAAUCGGCACCUCCUCCAGGCUCGUGGCAUCACCUGCAUUGUUAAUGCUACCAUUGAGAUCCCUAAUUUCAACUGGCCCCAAUUUGAGUAUGUUAAAGUGCCUCUGGCUGACAUGCCGCAUGCCCCCAUUGGACUGUACUUUGACACCGUGGCUGACAAGAUCCACAGUGUGAGCAGGAAGCACGGGGCCACCUUGGUGCACUGUGCUGCAGGGGUGAGCCGCUCAGCCACGCUGUGUAUCGCGUACCUGAUGAAAUUCCACAACGUGUGCCUGCUGGAGGCGUACAACUGGGUGAAAGCCCGGCGACCUGUCAUCAGGCCCAACGUAGGCUUCUGGAGGCAACUGAUAGACUACGAGCGCCAGCUCUUUGGGAAGUCGACAGUUAAAAUGGUACAGACACCUUAUGGCAUAGUUCCCGACGUCUAUGAGAAGGAGUCCCGACACCUGAUGCCUUACUGGGGGAUUUAGUGCCACUGAAGCCUGCGUCAGCAGCCCGAGCGGGGCCGGCAUCUGCUCCCCGCCGUCUGCUCCCUCUCCACUCUCUUCUCAAAUGGCUGACUUCUGGUUCUCCCUCAAGUGUUUUUUACACUGGGUGUUCAAAUUUAUUUUAAGAGAUAGGGAGGGAGGGGACAUAAAGGGAAUGCAUACAUUGCUAGUCACAUUUUUAAAAUUAACAUUUUGGAAUAGUGUUUAUGGAAAUCUUUAGCUUUUAAUCAUUUUUACCAAUUUGAACAGUUUAAUAAACUGGUUCUGCUCUCUUCUGAAUCUCAUGCCUUUGGCACCUUGGUAGGUGCAGGAGGAGCUCAGUGCAAAAAUCACUUUGGGGCCUCAUUAACCCUUUAGAGACAAGCUUUGCCCCAGGCUGCGGACCAGACAGAUGCUUAGGGAAGGUUGAUAACCAGCUUCAGUCUCUACUGGAUUAGCCCUACUCUUUCCUUUCCCCUCCAUUAUUUAGUGACUCUGUAAGUAAGUUAAAUACACCCUUAUUAUUUAGCUGUUAAGUAACUAUAAUGAAAUCUGCUGCAAAAUCUCUCUUGGAAUCCAUGUGCCCAGGAUUAUAUUAGCAUUAUUUUUAAUAAAUCUAUAUGCUUAACAUA